ACUUCCUGUUGCCUUAGGGGAACGUGGCUUUCCCUGCAGAGCCGGUGUCUCCGCCUGCGUCCCUGCUGCAGCAACCGGAGCUGGAGUCGGAUCCCGAACGCACCCUCGCCAUGGACUCGGCCCUCAGCGAUCCGCAUAACGGCAGUGCCGAGGCAGGCGGCCCCACCAACAGCACUACGCGGCCGCCUUCCACGCCCGAGGGCAUCGCGCUGGCCUACGGCAGCCUCCUGCUCAUGGCGCUGCUGCCCAUCUUCUUCGGCGCCCUGCGCUCCGUACGCUGCGCCCGCGGCAAGAAUGCUUCAGACAUGCCUGAAACAAUCACCAGCCGGGAUGCCGCCCGCUUCCCCAUCAUCGCCAGCUGCACACUCUUGGGGCUCUACCUCUUUUUCAAAAUAUUCUCCCAGGAGUACAUCAACCUCCUGCUGUCCAUGUAUUUCUUCGUGCUGGGAAUCCUGGCCCUGUCCCACACCAUCAGGUCAGAAGGCAUCUCUCUGCAACAUUUGAAGCAGCUUUCUCGGGAACCAGUACAGGGUCUUGGAUGAGAACAUGACUUUUGGCAUCAUUCAGAGCCAGGUUUGAAUCCUGGCUAUAAAACUCAAGGGACUCUUUCCCCUGCACACUGUAGAUGACUAGGACAAGAACAAUGACCUCUCUGGGCCACAGUUUCCUUAUAGACAUGAUGAGGAUCUGGUGGGUGUUUCCACCACCACAGCUGUUGGGAAAGUGAUUUGUGAGCAGUAAUGUCAUGUUAGUUGUGACAGUACUCAGGUGAGUAACACCAGUACCACCUGCCGGGUGUUGUGGCCUAGCUGUGUGCUAAGUGCCAUGUUGGGCUCCUCACACAUGAUCGUGUUUCGUAAGGAGCCAGAGGCAGCAUAGUGAAAAGUUAGGAGCGUGGGCUCUGGCAUUUGACUACCUUACUUUGAGUCCAGACUCUGCCACUUAAUAGCUCUGUGAUCUUGGGCAAGUUACUUAAUCUCUCUGGCCUCAAUUUCCUGGUGAAUGUGGAGAAAAAUAAUAGUGCCCUUCCCAUGGGGUCAUGUGGAAAGCUUUUAGCACAGUAUCUGGUGAUUUAAAGUGUUCAGUAACUAUUAGCUGUUACUGUCAUUAUCUGUGUUAACCUGCCAGACAACCUUAUAUGGGUUGCUUUUGCUUUCACACCUGUAUGAUAGUCAUGGAAACUGAAGCCCAGAGAGGUUAAGAAAUUUGCUAGGAUCACACCACUAAUAAGCAACAGAGCCAGGAUUCAAACCCAGGUGUGGCUCCAGAGCCCAUCCUCUUCCCACUGCUACCCUAACUCAAACUGCCACAUGCUCGUGUCCUUUCAGUGGGGAGAGUGGUUCAUUAGAGGGGGUUGCUACUUUUAUUUUGGACAGGCCAGUUCUCCAUUCUGCAGGACUAUCCCAUGUAUUACAAACAGUUGGCAACCUUGCCCUGCUCACCAAAUGGGAGUUGCAUACCAGUAUUCCCCAGCUUGUGACUACAGAGAUGUCCCAGUAUGUUUCUUUCUGCCCCGUUGAAGAGGUGCAGCCUCAGGCUGAGAAACACUGAUAGACCAAGAGGUGGCCAGGGUUCCCAGAAGGAAGGAACUCACCUUGAACUUAGCUUUCUUUGAAGGGUAGGAAACCUGGAAGACGUACAAAGGAGGGAGAGGUCAGGUGCUAGAAAGUUUGUGCACAUUGAGGGCAUGGGCAGAAUCUGCUCCCAAAAGCAUUGAAAGCCAAUAUGAGGCCAGGUGGUGGCUCAUGCCUGUAAUCCCAGCACUUUGGGAGGCCAAGGCAGGCGGAUCACAAGGUCAGGAGAUUGAGACCAUCCUGGCCAACAUGGUGAAACCCCGUCUCUACUAAAAAUACAAAAAAAUUAGCUGGGCAUGGUGGUGCAUGCCUGUAGUCCCAGCUACUCAGGAGGCUGAGGUAGGAGAAUCAUUGAACCUGGGAGGCGGAGGUUGCAGUGAGCCGAGAUUGCACCACUGCAUUCCAGCCUGGCGACAGAGUGAGACUCCAUCUCAAAAAAAAAAAAAAAGCCAAUAUGAAUGUGGCUUCAUUCUUCUAGGCACACUGGCAGGACAGUGUGGUAGUCAGGAGCACAGGGUCAAGAGGCAGGCAGCCUUGGGACAAACACCUGGUGCUGCCAGCUCUAAUAUGUGUAAAUUACUCAAGCUCUGAGCAUAGUUCUUCUACCUAUAAAAUGGAGAGACUACAGGUACCUCCUCAGAGGUGUGGGGAGGGUCUAGUGAGCCCCAGGCUGUAACAUCCCUAGAGCACAGUGCCAAGCACACAGUGAGCCUAGUGGCUGGCCCAGGGUUACACAGCUGAGACUUCACCUCUGGUCUUCCCACUGAGGUCAUUGUUGUCCUCACCUGCACUGACUCUUCACCCACAAAAUUCUAUUCUAGCUAGCUUGGGAGAAUUCUAGUCCAGCCCCGCAUCCUGAAAAAUGGAGGCCCAGGGAACCUGAGUGACUUGGACCCAACCAAGAUAAUGGCAGGCCCAGUCGCCCUUGCUCACAGGACAAACCAGUCCUUUCGUGGUGGACCUGGGGUGGGGUGGGGGCAGUCACUUGCAGACAUUGGGUGUCCUCCUUUCCCAUGCUGAUUAGGAUCCUCCCCAACUGUAGCCCAUCCUACCCCAGCAUCUGUGAGACGCUUGAGACCCCCAAGUCUCCCCACAGCCCAGCCUCCACCUCAGAGAGCCCAGUGGGUUUUGAAAGCCACUGUUAGGCUGUGUGCUGAGGAACUGAUUAUUUAAUGUUAUAGCAACAACCCUACAAUGAAGAUCUUAUCUCUACCCAGCUGCCUAGGCAGGGUAUUUUGAACCUUUAUCAUCUUGACACCAAAGACUUUUUUUCCCUUUUAGAAUAAUAACUAAGGGACAUUGUCCCAAAUUUCUCAUAGAUGAGUAAUCUAUGUCAAGAAAUAAUUGAGGGUGGGCACGGUGGCUCACACCUGUAAUCGCAGCACUUUGUGAGGCCAAGGCAGGUGGAUCACCUGAGGUCAGGAGUUCAAGACCAGCCUGGGCAACAUGGUGAAACCUUGUCUACUAAAAAUACAAAAAAGUAGCCGGGUGUGAUGACGCACCCAGCUACUCGGGAGGCUGAGGCAGGAGAAUCACUUGAACCCAGGAGGUGGAGGUCGCAAUGAGUCAAGAUCGCACCACUGCACUCCAGCCUGGGUGACAGAGGGAGACUCCAUCUCAAAAAAAAAAAAAAGAAAUAAUUGUCUAUCUGUCUUUUAGCCACUUCAUAAUUUUUAGAGAUAGAUAUUAUCAACAGAAAAUAAAACCAACAGCAGCUAAAACUGCACAUGGUAAAAUGUAUGAGUGACUAGAAACUAACAGAAGAAUAAUUUUCUUAAUGAAAUUUAGAGCAACAAAAUUUGACCUGGGAAAACCAUACCUUUUAAAAAUAAUGGAUCACCUGGGCAUGGUGGUUCACACCUGUCAUCCCAGCACUUUGGGAACCCUAGGCUGUUGGAUCACCUGAGCUCAGGAGUUCAAGACCAGCCUGGGCAACAUGUUGAGACCCUGUCUCCACAAAAAAUACAAAAAUUAGCCGGGUAUGGUGGUGCGUGCCUGUGGUCCCAACUGCUCGGUAGGCUGAGGUGGGAUGAUCGCGUGAACCUGGGAGGCAGAGAGGUUGCAGUGAGCUGUGAUCAUGCCACUGCACUCCAGCCUGGGUAACAGAGUAAGACCCCAUCUGAAAAAUAUAAAAAAAAAAAAAAAAGAAUAAUGGAUGGCCAUAGGCAGAAGGUAUGCUUACCAUAUGGGGUUAAAGCUGGUCCACUAAAAAAUUUGAUGGGGACCAAAAACUGUCAGAUGAAGGAAAUCAUUAUUGUAAAAUUAACAUGAAAAAGAACUGAAUCCAGUGAAAAUAAUUUUAGUAAGUAGGGGAUGAUUUGAUCAUGCUUUUUAGAAAGUUGGUCUACCAAUUAAAUGGAUGUUUCAAUUAAA